AUAGUAGCGAGAGGCGCUAGCUGCCAGCUCCAGCAGCCCAGAUCGCGCAGUAUUUCUGCGUGGCACCGGUGCGGAUGCGGCUGUAAAGCAGUGGUCACCGCCUCCGGGAGCCCACUUCUAUGUGGAGAGGGGAGCACCCAGAGAGGGUCUUAGGAGUCCUCCCAUGGCUUCACAGAAGCAGAUGGAGGUAGUGACCAAAGGAACUGGGUUCCGGCGCCGCCCCAAGACCAUCACUUACACCCCGGGGACCUGCGAGCUGCUCAGAGUGAUGAUGAAGGAAUCCAAACUGACGAACAUCCAGCAGCGCCACAUCAUGGACAUCAUGAAAAGAGGAGAUGCUUUGCCCCUACAGUGCAGCCCAACAUCCAGCCAGAGAGUCUUACCUUCCAAGCAAAUAGCCUCGCCCAUCUACCUGCCUCCCAUCCUCGCAGCCCGUCCCCACCUCCGGCCUGCCAACAUGUGUCAAGCCAAUGGGGCCUACAGCCGGGAGCAGUUCAAGCCUCAAGCCACCAGGGAUUUGGAGAAGGAGAAACAAAGACUCCAAAAUAUCUUUGCCACAGGGAAGGACAUGGAGGAACGGAAAAGAAAGGCCCCUCCUGCACGACAGAAGGCUCCAGCCCCUGAGCUAGACCGAUUUGAAGAGCUGGUGAAGGAAAUCCAGGAGAGGAAAGAAUUCCUGGCUGACAUGGAGGCCCUGGGACAGGGCAAACAGUACCGAGGAAUCAUCCUUGCUGAAAUCUCCCAGAAACUCCGGGAAAUGGAAGACAUUGACCACAGAAGGAGUGAGGAACUUAGGAAGGGUCUUGCCACCACUUAAUCUGUCUCCAGAGACGGGCAGGGUAGCCCAAGCUCGACCACUGGAGUCCACUCCUCUGCCAGGCAGGGCCAUCCUCAGGCCAGCCCAUCCUACCAGCCUUCUGCCACGUCAGGUGGUGGCAUAGCACUGCCCUGCAGUACCCCAAGGCAUACUCAGCAGCCUAGCCCCUGCCCCGGAAUGCAGAUGGAGCCUCUGAGACUCACAGCCCCGUCCGCAGAGAAGCAAAGCCCGAGCAUCCCUACUAGGACAUGUGUCUAAAGGUAUCCACUGGGCCUGCUUCCCACCACUUCUGACCUGUGGCCUGUUCAUUUAGUUUUCUGAAUUCAGGAAUGAAUAUGAUUCCUUUCUUCCUGUUUUAGGAUUUACUUAUUUGAUUUCUUACCGCCUUAGGCAAGUAUUCAACCACAAUGAUUAACUGGCCAAUAAAACAUAUUUAACGUGGGUCAUUACAAGCACCAUUUUGUUUUCAGAGGGAUAAGCUUAUUUGUUCAAGGCAUUAGACUUUGUCAAGCCCAGAUGGUUUCUAGCUACCUGUUUGCAUAUUUCAAGUGGCAACGGGAACCAACCUCUUGGGCACCCCAUGGCUGGCUGCUGUGGCGGGUGCUGAAUUCCACUCUGUUAAUGAUCUCAAUAAACCUCUGCAACGGUUCAUUAUCCCUCUGUGAAAACUAAGUCUCAACAAGAUACCACAACCAAGGGCAUUUACCUGGCAAGCAGUGCAUUCAGGAUUAAAAGUUGGCUUUAGCUUUAUGUCUUUCCACUAUACCCAUGGCCACAGAAAGAAACAUGAAAAGGUGGGAGCGACCUAGAGCCCUGGCCUGGGAGUUCCAAUCCCUGCAUGUGCCGCGUGACCUUUCUUGGGCAAAACCCACCAGCUCCGUGCUUGUGCAUCUGCGAGGCCCUGCUGGGAAGGAGUCACCUGACACCUUGUCCUGUACACAGCACAUCUGUCCCCCUCCCCUCUGGCUCCUGACACCCACGAUCCCUGCCUUCUCCGGUAUUCUGUCAUUUGCUUGUCCCACUAAAUCACCAAAAUAUUUUGGAAAUAUCAACCUUGUCUCGGGCACCUGGAGGGAGUCCCAUAAUCCCAUCAGGUCACAUGACCCAAGUUUCGGUUUGCAGAAU